GUAACGGACGGCGGAGGCUACGUGAAGAGAGGCGCGGCGUGACUGAGCUACGGUUCUGGCUGCGUCCUAGAGGCAUCCGGGGCAGUAAAACCGCUGCGAUCGCGGAGGCGGCGGCCAGGCCGAGAGGCAGGCCGGGCAGGGGUGUCGGACGCAGGGCGCUGGGCCGGGUUUCGGCUUCGGCCACAGGUAAGGAGCGGGCCAGGACGCGCUCGUCGGCGUGGCCGGGCCAGGCCGAGCGGUGACUCCGAGUUGCUUGGCCUGUAGCCCGGUCCGGUUGAGAUAAUUGUAAUGGUUUGGGGGAACUUUCCCACGGAGCUGUGAGCAAAUGAUAGCCAAAAGGGCAGAGUUAGAGGAAAUGUACAGUGUGUGCCGGAGGAUGACAUUAGGAUGUAUUGAUUCUCUUGGGUGGGGAGAAACUAGGCAAAGGGGUUUAAUAGAAGCAAAAACCUCUGUGGCCAGUCUCUUCUGGAGGUUUCUAAAAUGAAACGUGUUUGUAUCCAACACAUAUAAAGAGACAGAGGAAAGUCUGCAUGAUUUCCAGAAUACUCGUUUUGGCCGUUGUCAGGAAGACCUAAUCUAAAAUGACAACAAGGAAUGAUGGCCUCACUCAGUCCUCUUUCCUCAAGUCUAGACUCAGUCGCUGAGGAACUAUUGGAUGAGCUUGCAGAAAAUAAUCAAACCAGACUUGUUAGCGCUUGUGUGAAUUUUCCUUGGUCCUGUGUUGCUUGCUUCAGGAGUCAUAGAGGCUGGGUGGUCUGGCAAGGACUUGUGCAUUUGAGAACUGACAGGUGCAGCGGAGACUUCUAAGAGGGAAAACCAAGCUUUUUUUCUCAAGGUGCAAUGAAAGCCUUCCACACUUUCUGUGUUGUCCUUCUGGUGUUUGGGAGUGUCUCUGAAGCCAAGUUUGAUGAUUUUGAGGAUGAGGAGGACAUAGUAGAGUAUGAUGAUAAUGACUUCGCUGAAUUUGAGGAUGUCAUGGAAGACUCUGUUACUGAAUCUCCUCAACGGGUCAUAAUCACUGAAGAUGAUGAAGAUGAGACCACUGUGGAGUUGGAAGGGCAGGAUGAAAACCAAGAAGGAGAUUUUGAAGAUGCAGAUACCCAGGAGGGAGAUACUGAGAGUGAACCAUAUGAUGAUGAAGAAUUUGAAGGUUAUGAAGACAAACCAGAUACUUCUUCUAGCAAAAAUAAAGACCCAAUAACGAUUGUUGAUGUUCCUGCACACCUCCAGAACAGCUGGGAGAGUUAUUAUCUAGAAAUUUUGAUGGUGACUGGUCUGCUUGCUUAUAUCAUGAAUUACAUCAUUGGGAAGAAUAAAAACAGUCGCCUUGCACAGGCCUGGUUUAACACUCAUAGGGAGCUUUUGGAGAGCAACUUUACUUUAGUGGGGGAUGAUGGAACUAACAAAGAAGCCACAAGCACAGGAAAGUUGAACCAGGAGAAUGAGCACAUCUAUAACCUGUGGUGUUCUGGUCGAGUGUGCUGUGAGGGCAUGCUUAUCCAGCUGAGGUUCCUCAAGAGACAAGACUUACUGAAUGUCCUGGCCCGGAUGAUGAGGCCAGUGAGUGAUCAAGUGCAAAUAAAAGUAACCAUGAAUGAUGAAGACAUGGAUACCUACGUAUUUGCUGUUGGCACACGGAAAGCCUUGGUGCGACUACAGAAAGAGAUGCAGGAUUUGAGUGAGUUUUGUAGUGAUAAACCUAAGUCUGGAGCAAAGUAUGGACUGCCGGACUCUUUGGCCAUCCUGUCAGAGAUGGGAGAAGUCACAGACGGAAUGAUGGAUACAAAGAUGGUUCACUUUCUUACACACUAUGCUGACAAGAUUGAAUCUGUUCAUUUUUCAGACCAGUUCUCUGGUCCAAAAAUUAUGCAAGAGGAAGGUCAGCCUUUAAAGCUACCUGACACUAAGAGGACACUGUUGUUUACAUUUAAUGUGCCUGGCUCAGGUAACACUUACCCAAAGGAUAUGGAGGCACUGCUACCCCUGAUGAACAUGGUGAUUUAUUCUAUUGAUAAAGCCAAAAAGUUCCGACUCAACAGAGAAGGCAAACAAAAAGCAGAUAAGAACCGUGCCCGAGUAGAAGAGAACUUCUUGAAACUGACACAUGUGCAAAGACAGGAAGCAGCACAGUCUCGGCGGGAGGAGAAAAAAAGAGCAGAGAAGGAGCGAAUCAUGAAUGAGGAAGAUCCUGAGAAACAGCGCAGGCUGGAGGAGGCUGCAUUGAGGCGUGAGCAAAAGAAGUUGGAAAAGAAGCAAAUGAAAAUGAAACAAAUCAAAGUGAAAGCCAUGUAAAGCCAUCCCAGAGAUUUGAGUUCUGAUGCCACCUGUAAGCUCUGAAUUCACAGGAAACAUGAAAAACGCCAGUCCAUUUCUCAACCUUAAAUUUCAGACAGUCUUGGGCAACUGAGAAAUCCUUAUUUCAUCAUCUACUCUGUUUGGGGUUUGGGGUUUUACAGAGAUUGAAGAUACCUGGAAAGGGCUCUGUUUCAAGAAUUUUUUUUUCCAGAUAAUCAAAUUAUUUUGAUUAUUUUAUAAAAGGAAUGAUCUAUGAAAUCUGUGUAGGUUUUAAAUAUUUUAAAAAUUAUAAUACAAAUCAUCAGUGCUUUUAGUACUUCAGUGUUUAAAGAAAUACCGUGAAAUUUAUAGGUAGAUAACCAGAUUGUUGCUUUUUGUUUAAACCAAGCAGUUGAAAUGGCUAUAAAGACUGACUCUAAACCAAGAUUCUGCAAAUAAUGAUUGGAAUUGCACAAUAAACAUUGCUUGAUGUUUUCUUGUAUGUCUACAUUAAACUUGAGAAAAAGUAAAAAUUAGAACACUGUAUGUAGUAAUGAAAUUUCAGGGACCCAGAACAUAAUGUAGUAUAUGUUUUUAGGUGGGAGAUGCUGAUAACAAAAUUAAUAGGAAGUCUGUAGGCAUUAGGAUACUGACAUGUACAUGGAAAAUUCUAGGGACAGGAGCAUCAUUUUUUCCUUACCUGAUACCACGAACCAGUGACAACGUGAAUGCUGUAUUUUAAGUGGUUGUAUGUUUAUUUUCUUGAGUAACAAAUGCAUGAAAAAUUAAUGCUUCACCUAGGUAAGAUCAUUGGUCUGUGUGAAAUCACAAAUGUUUUUUCCUUCUUGGUUGCUGCAGCCUGGUGGAUGUUCAUGGAGAAGCUCUGUUCUCUAUAUUAUGGCUGUGUGCCGUUGCUUCUCCCUCUGCUUUUAUCUUUUCCACAGUUGAGGCUGGGUAUGUUCUUUCAAAGAAAUGGCCAUGAAUAUGUGUAAGUAUACUUUUGAAAAUGAGCUUUCCUAAACUAUUGAGAGUUCUUUCCACCUCUUGCGGAACCAACUCUUGGAGGAGAGGCCCAUGUAUCUGCACGAGCACUUAGCUUGUUCAGAUCUCUGCAUUUUAUAAAUGCUUCUUACCAAGAAAGCAUUUUUAGGUCAUUGCUUGUACCAGGUAAUUUUUGCCGGGGAUGGGUAAGGGUUGGGUUUUCUGGUGGGAGUGGGGUGGUGGGUAUUUUUUGUUGAUGCUUUAGUGCAGGCCUGUUCUGAGGCAAUAACAAGUUGCUGUGAAAACAGCAUGUGCUGCUGCCUUUGUAACUGCAUGGAAACUUUUCACAUGGGUUUUUCUCCAAGUUAAUACAGAAAUAUGUAAACUGAGAGAUGCAAAUGUAAUAUUUUUAACAGUUCAUGAAGUUGUUAUUAAAAUAACUAACAUAAAACUUAAUUACUUUAAUAUUAUAUAAUUAUAGUAGUGGCCUUGUUUUACAAACCUUUAAAUUACAUUUUAGAAAUCAAAGUUGAUAGUCUUAGUUAUCUUUUGAGUAAGAAAAGCUUUCCUAAAGUCCCAUACAUUUGGACCAUGGCAGCUAAUUUUGUAACUUAAGCAUUCAUAUGAACUACCUAUGGACAUCUAUUAAAGUGAUUGACAAAA